CUCUCGCCGCGUCGCCGGUGCCUGCGCCUCCCGCUCCACCUCGCUUCUUCUCUCCCGGCCGAGGCCCGGGGGACCAGAGCGAGAAGCGGGGACCAUGUUCCGACGCAAGUUGACGGCUCUCGACUACCACAACCCCGCCGGCUUCAACUGCAAAGAUGAAACAGAAUUUAGAAACUUCAUCGUUUGGCUUGAAGACCAGAAAAUCAGGCACUACAAGAUUGAAGACAGAGGGAAUUUAAGAAACAUCCACAGCAGCGACUGGCCCAAGUUCUUUGAAAAGUAUCUCAGAGAUGUUAACUGUCCUUUCAAGAUUCAAGAUCGACAAGAAGCUAUUGACUGGCUUCUUGGUUUAGCUGUUAGACUUGAAUAUGGAGAUAAUGCUGAAAAAUACAAGGAUUUAGUACCUGAUAAUUCAAAAACUGCUGACAAUGCAACUAAAAAUGCAGAACCAUUGAUCAAUUUGGAUGUAAAUAAUCCUGAUUUUAAGGCUGGUGUGAUGGCUUUGGCUAACCUGCUUCAGAUUCAGCGUCAUGAUGAUUACCUGGUAAUGCUUAAGGCAAUUCGGAUUUUGGUUCAGGAGCGCCUGACACAGGAUGCAGUUGCUAAGGCAAAUCAAACAAAAGAGGGCUUACCUGUUGCUUUAGACAAACAUAUUCUUGGUUUUGACACAGGAGAUGCAGUUCUUAAUGAAGCUGCUCAAAUUCUGCGAUUGCUGCACAUAGAGGAGCUCAGAGAGCUACAGACAAAAAUCAACGAAGCCAUAGUAGCUGUUCAGGCAAUUAUUGCUGAUCCAAAGACAGACCACAGACUGGGAAAAGUUGGAAGAUGAACACUUGAGGACUUCAGCUUCUCACCUACUUAGUACAGUUGGGAACCAUACACUUCUGGCAUGUUUGGAAAUCAAAAUGUCACAUUCUCGGGGGAGGAAGCCCAGAAAAUUGGGUAUGUUCUAGAGAUUUACCACCAUUGCUUAUUGCUUUUUUCUUUAAUAAAGUUUAGGAAAGUAGAAUUUUUAUUAUGUACUGUAUGUUUGCAUAAAUCACCUUUCUCCUUUGUGGUUAAGGCAUAUAUGCCAACCCCCAGCUUUGUCCUAGAGACAAUAUAGAUCCUUAAGUCAUAGGAAAACUUAAAACACUUUAUUGGAGUAAUCUAGAAAAUUUUAAAAUUGUUACAUCUUUGGUAUUUAUAAAUGUGAUACUUUACUUUCUGUGGGUACUUCUAUAGAGGCACUACAGGAUCAGAAAAUGCAAAUUGAAUCAUUUUAGCACCUUUUGAUAUAAAUAGAAAUGCACUGAUGCAGAGGUAAAAAAUCUUAGAACUUUUGUUGGGAAACUAUAAAUAAUUGGUCCUUUCCCAUCAGUUCUGCAUUGGCUUCUCCAACUGUCAAGGUUUAGGAUUAUAUUGUUAUAUUGAUCACAUGUGCUUUAAUUUCUUGGCCAGAAGGAAUCCAUGGCAAAAAUCAGGUUUAGAGUCUUAAACUCUAAUUCUUAGUUGAAUGAAUUUGAUCUUUUAAAUAUUAAUGAUAAAUGUUUACAAGAAGUUGCUUUAAUAAGCAACAGUUAAAAUUCUGUUACCUUUUUAAACUUGCAAUAACAACCUUCAUUUUUAAAAAUACAGUAGUAAAGAUUGAGGUAUCAGCUUUUCACAAAAGUCUUUUUGCACUACAAAAUGUUCAUCUUGGAUGCUCAGGAACGUCUAAUGGCCAAUUCCUUUUUUACUUUCUUUGCCUUUGCAGUCACUGUUCUUUAGGGUCCAGGUUCUGAUUGUAAACUCCAAGUCUUCCUUUACAUUACUGUACUUACUUUCUUCCUGUGAGAGAAGAGCAGGGGUGGGACAGGGUGGUGGGUGAGUAUAUUGUAACCAAGUUGCAACAGCAAGUCUUUGCAUUUUGUGUAUAAACUAGGUAGAUUUAAGGUAGUAAAGACUGGCCCUCAGGGCAGGAAGAAGGCAAUGGUGGCAGUGUCACAGGCAGCAGGGGUAAUCAAAUACCAUAUAUAUCCCUUCUCUACCCUGCUAAUUUAAAGGAGCAUCCUAAAGCAUACUUUUUACCUGUUGGGCAGUAGGGGUAGACUGCAGUUAUCCCGUAGAGGUGAGAUCGUUGUUCUGGGAGAUACUCAUCAGUAAACUGGCCACUAUGUUUAUUUACUGAUACAACACCAUCCCUGGUAACAGAAAGGAAGAGUGAAUUCAGGGACAGUCAUUUACUAGAUAAAGAAGUCAGUCAGCCACAGAAAAUCAGUUGCAAUAGAGGAAAAUUUCUGGCAGCCUUCUCUGUCCCAGGGCUGGUGCUAAAGCCAUACUGAAGUUUGAAGACCAUUGCUCUAAAUCCAUUGCUCAUCUCUAGCUGCAUGUUAGAAUCACAUGAUGAGCUAUCAAAUCAGAGUUGUAGGGCAUGGUGUAAAGGGCUUAGACUUUAAUGUUCCACAGUUCCUCAUUUGAGAACUAGUCUAAAUAGUAUUUUUCGGUCCCUCAGACAAUAUGUCCACAGUGUCAAAAGCCAACUUAAGCCCUGUAAUAUAGCUCAUGGUAUCAAGGGUAGUCUUAUUCUCUAAAGAACAUAUUUAGAUUAAUAUGCUCCCUUUUGAGACAUUAUCCAAUAGCUUUGCUACUUUUUAAGCUAUAUGUGAGCAAUACCAUUCGAUUUCUGGGUGAAGUAAAAGGAUGAUUUCAAAAACAUGAAAGGAUGAAAAACAUCCUUGAAGGAUCUUAUCUGCCAAUGAGGAGGUGAUGAAACAAAAGCCUCAGAGGGCUUAAUGAGUCAAGUCAGGUACUGACUUUUGGUAAAACAAGUGGUGUGUCCUCUGGAACAGUUGGCCUUUUCAGGCUUGUCCAGAAUUUGUGGGGCUCACCUCCUCCAGUCUGUGUGGUAGAAGUGAUCUGCAUAGCUUACGAUGCUGAAGGGGUACUUGAGGUUGUUUUGAAUGACACGCCGUCCAGUUCCAUCAGGUAGUGUACACUCCAGUUUUUUGGUUCCUUUUAAAACAAAGGGGGAAAAUGAGGUCCUUCAGCUGCUUUGCCAAAAAUGAUAGUGACAUAGUGAUAGUGACACAGUGAUAGAAUGGGGAAAUAGGAUAUUUUACUUCCAUUACAGUCAUAGAUUAGCAACUGUAAAAUUACCUGUCCUAUUACUAGUCUCCAGUUUUUAGUAGAGAUUCAAACUUUCAAUCCUUUUUUGGAAGACAGGAUUGCAUUUACUGAAAUCUGGUAAGUUUCUGCCAAAGUAGGGCAUUAAACAUAAUUAUUUUUAUAAUUUGUGUGAUUUCAAGCCUUAGCUUAUAAAUUAUAACAUCUGGGUAAAUACUUGCCCUUUGUAAGCUAUGUCUAUAAUUACUGAGGCAACCUUUUAACCAAAAUCCUUAGUAUUUUUAAAAUAUUUUCUAGGUAGGAGGAAAAAAGUGACUAAAAUGGUAACAUAACUCAUAUUUCAAUGUAAAGGAAUCAGUCUUAAAAAUUUUUACAAUAGCUAAACCAUUCAAGAAUUUCCAAGUUUCACAUUUCUCAUGGAGCCGAUUUAAAUUUCAAAUCCUUUUAAGAAAUGUAACUUGUUUUAAACAACUGGGUUAUAAAAGUGACCUAUGUACAUUAGGCCCUUUUAUUAGAUUACAAAUUCAAGAACAGUCUUUUUCAUAUUCUUUAGUAUAGAACUAGACACACAGCAUUUUUUCAGUUGUGCUGAUAAAAGCAAACAAAUGUAGGUUGCUAAUACCCAUGUUAUUACUGAAGGAAGCUACCCUGCUACAAUGCUUUCCAAAGAAUGUCCUUAGCAUUAUAACAGAUGUUUAUAGGUAAGUUAUAGUGACCCUCUCCCCGCAUAAGAAUAACUUCACUUAAGUUUGUCAAUUCAACAAUGGCUAAUUCUUUUAACUGUUAAAAAUAUGCCAGGCACUCAUGGUCAGGCAAGCAGUACAAACUUACUGCUUGAUAUAUCCUUCCCUCCACCCAAACCCCAGAAAGUUCAUUUUAAGACUCAUUUACUAGUACUUAAAUUUACUAGUACUUAAAAGUUUACAGACCAAAGAAAGGAGAUCUAAGUGAUGGGAUUUCAUUUUGUAGUAAAAUCUGUUAGUGCUCACAUUCACUGUGAUGAGAGGUUAUCUAUUUGCAUUCCAUCAGUAGUAUUACCUGCAUCUGCCCAGCAGAGCAGUUUAGAGAAAGGGUCAAAGGUUAAGCCAUUGGGCAAUCCAAUGUCUGUAUUGAUCAGAAUUCUUCUGUUUUCUCCAUCUAAAGAUGACGUUUCAAUUUUAGGAGCUUCUCUAUUCCAGUCUGUCCAGUACAAGUUGCUGUAAGUUAAAAAUCAAGAUUGUAAAAGAAUAGCCAUGUAGCCUGUGGUAGGCAGCAUCUAAGCAGCCCCCAGUGAUCUCCAUCUCCUCAUGUAUUAUAGCCUUAAGCAAUCCCCUUGAGUUUGGGCUGCAUUAGUAGUGUCUUGCUUCUUCUAGUGCAUAGAGUAUAGCAGAAGUGAUAGGCUAUCACUGCCGAUAUUCGGUCUCAAAAAACUGGUUUCUGCCUUAGGGGCUCUCUCUUGCUCCCUUUGAGGGAAGCUGGAUGCCAUGUUGCAAGCUACCCUGUAAAGGGGAACAUGUGCCAAGGAACUGAUGUCCUUGAGGGCUGUUGGCCAGAGACAUUAGUCUUGCCUGUAGCCCAUGUGAGCAUGCUUGGGCUGUGUCUUCCCCGAGCUGAGCCUUGUGAUCACUGCAGUUUGGCCAUUACCUGAUUGCAGCCUUGUGAGAGACUCCAUGCCUGAGGGAGCUCGGUGAAGACACACUUGGAUUCCUGACUCACAGAAACUGUGAGACUAAAUGUUAUCUUACACUGCUGAGGGUUUGGGCAAUUUCUUACACAGCAGUAGGUAACUAAUACACAGCCAUAUUCCACUUUUACCUGUAUCACAAGGUUUUCUGAUUAUUGUCACUAUGUGGGAGAAGUCAUUACUAAGUUACUAUCAGAAUCCCUGCCUCCAAGAUACCCCUUGACUCAACUGCCCCAAAACCCUCCGUUUGUUGAAGUCUUGAAUUGGAUCUUGGGUUUUAGAAUAGAAACAAAUACAGCUGUUAGGAAUGGCUUCGAUACAAACUAUGGAACUUGAAGAGAUGUGGACCAGGGAUUUGAGAAGGAAACUGUUCUUUCUUCUGCCAAAAAUACAAUUUGGUACUUGAAGGGGUACCUGGCACCCAGGGAUGGAAACAUUUUAAGUUAAGCACUUUACCUUUUAAAUGCCACGUUAAAAAUGAAAUAUAUUCAUAACAGAUACUAACGAGGAAAUAUGGUCCUAUUAAGUGGAAAUAGGUUAUAAGGAAACAAACAGGUUUAUCGUUAGAGCAGAAAUAAUGUUGAAAGCACUUUUUAUAAAAUACUAUUUUAUAAAAGCUAUAGAAGCUUUGAAUAAAUCAGUUGGGCUACAGAGAACCUCAGUGAGAGGAGAGGAAGAAACCAUAGGUUUCCCCUGUUGCGAAUUUCAUCCCUUAUGCCCAACAGAUGAAGCAGAGAGAAGCUGAGAGCAAAAGCUAGAAAGCAGUUUCCACUUUGCGCUAAGGUGGAGGUGGCCAGAGGGUACAGCAUGCAUAUCAUUGCUUCAUCGCUUCUGAUCAGUCUCCUCCCCAAAAUGAUUUAAUAUCAUCAACAACAAUAAGUCUGAAACAAGCUCACACAGAUAUUUGGUGUAAAUUAUUUGGGGAUUGCCAGAGGAAGAAAGUUGUAAAGGUGAAAUCUAUAGAAAGCAAAUGAGAAAUAUGCAGGAAGGCUUGACAACCAUUCUGUUACGCAGUUGAAGGAGAUGUAAUUACAUGUGUUAUAUUGCAACCUGGUUCAAGGUGGGUUUUCUUUUUAUUAAAAAUUCAAGUCCUUUAGCAUUUAUAUUUGCUGUCUGGAUAAGAAAGUUCUACUUUCAUAUUUAAACUCAUGGCUGUGAUGUGGAUUUCAGCUUAAAAGUAUGCUUUUUCCCCAGACUCCAGAGACAUGGCCAAAGUUUCAUUGCCUACAAGAUGGCAGCUCUCCCCAGUUUUCAGGUCAAGCACCAAGAAGGAAUAAGGGGCCGGGCGCAGUGGCUCAUACCUAUAAUCCCAGCACUUUGGGAGGCCAAGGCAGGUGGAUCACCCAGGGUCAGGAGUUGGAGACCAAAAUGGCGAAACCCUGUCUCGACUAAAAAUACAAAAAUUAGCUGGGCAUGGUGGCACAUGCCUGUAGUCCCAGCUACUUGGGAGGCUGAGGCAGGAGAAUUGCUUGAACCCGGGAGAUGGAGGUUGUAGUCAGCCGAGACUGUGCCACUGCACCCCAGCCUCGGCAACAAAGCAAGACCUUGUCUCAAAAAAAAGAAAAAAAAAAGAAAAAAGGACCUUCCAAAUGUCCAAAUGUCAGAAAGGCAAGCCUAUGCAAAGAGUUUUUAAGAGGGCUAUUAAUUCCUGUUAAGUCAACUGGAAUAGAGAAGGAUACAGGUACUUUUCCUGUGUGUAGAACCCAAAGUUUGAAACCACCUUUGAGGCACUGCACUAAGUAUUUCAUAGUCAAAAAGCACUUACCUGAAAAUUAAAGCUGAAGGUUUUCUUUACUGAUUUGAAGGGCAUCUGGGAAUUUCAUUUCGUAGAAACUCCACUUAAACAUGGCAAGAGUUUCUCAAGAUAUAAAAAUUCUCCCUGAUUGUAACAAGUACUGAGACAGUGAACAAAUCCUGUAUGUCACAUUUGAUGACCUUAGCAAUUAUACAGACAGGGAAAAUGUUUAUCUUGAUUUCUGCUACAGCAACACUGAAGCCAGAGGUGUCUGAGCUUUGGCUAAUGUCACUUGAUGUAGGUCAGCCCUACUGUGAGCGUCAACCCUGGUUUCUAAAUGUGCUGCUGGAGGAAUCCCACUUCACUUCCAGUUUAAGUGUCAGCUGAGGCCUCGCCUGAUCAUUUGAUUCAGAGUAGCCCUAGUUCUCACAACACUAUCUGAAUUUUCUACAUAUCACAUCACAGACUAAUAUUGUUUAUACCAGUCUUGUUUCCUCCUAAUAAAAUAUAAGUGCCAUGAAAGAA